ACCCGCACCUUCCCCUCCUGGAAGAGGCUGAGAAGUAAAGAUCAGGAACAAGGAGGAGGAGGAGCUUCCCAGACGUGUAGAGCUUAUGAAGUUUAGGAAGCAGCUUCCCAGACAUGUAGAGCUUAUGGAGAGGUGAGGGAGCCAAUCUCAGCCACAUUCAGCUUCCUGGAGAGAAUGACCAAAGGGCGACGCUUCAACCCACCUUCAGACAAGGAUGGGAGAUGGUUCCCUCACAUCGGGCUAACGCAAAAGACACCAGAAUCCAUCACCAGUGCUACGUCAAAAGAGCCCCAGAGUCCACACUUGCCUCGGCAAGCGGAGGGGAAGCUGCCGCCCAUAUACAAAGUCCGGGAGAAGCAAGCAGUGAAUAACCAGUUCCCCUUCUCCGUGCAUGACAAUCGGCACAGCUUGGAGAACUCUGGAUGCUACCUUGACUCCGAGCUAGCAUCAGAAUGUUCAGUCCAAGAACAAUGAUUUCUACUCCACUUGGGCACUGAUCUGGCUGUAACAUCUGCAGGGGACAAUCCCAGUUCUGAACGGAAAAAACAACUUUGCUCAUUAUCCACGUUCCAUAUAGCUACUGACGGGAUAAUAAGUGACCACAGCGGAAUACUACGCCUUCUCUGCUGAGAACACAUGGUUGUAAUUCCUUUGGCCUGAAGGAGAAUCACUGAAGCCAUUUUAAACAUUCUUCUGCUGUUUAUAGCCUUUGUCUAAGAUGCCAUGACUGGUAUCGGCCAUGAGUGGCAUAUCCAAUCCCUCUCUAACAUCUGCCGUUAUAGUUCCCAAAGAGGAUUGAGAAGUCUCAACAUAAUCUCACAGGAGAAAUCUUAUUGUUCCUCCAAAGAAUAUUUUGUAUUGAAAGCAAUGCCUCAUAUUUAUGACAUUCUAGAUGUUUAGAGAAAGGAUUUGACUCUGUUGGAUAACUUCAAUCAACGAGGAUAGUCUGGGUUAAAGCAAUCAUGUUUGCCAACUGAAUCUGGGUUGUUUUACAGCUCAUUCCUUAAUAUGGCCACAGCCCCUCCCACCCUCAGCUUCCCCCACCCCCCCACAUUGCCCCAUUCCCUUUGGGACAGGUGAUGUAGCCACAGUAUCAUGUGUAUUGGUAUGAACACAAUGUAAGACAUGCCCAAAGACCUUAUGUAUUUACUCAUCAUUCGGUGACAAUUUUUUUUUAUCACAGCCCUAACUCUGUGUUAAGUACUAUGCUGGCUUCUGGGGUACAAGCAUGAGUGGUAACAGACCCCAAUGCUGCCUGUAGUGCAUCCAGCAUAGACUGUCAGGCAGUGAGAUGCAGCAGGCCCCUUGCAAUAGCUGAGAUUUGGAGCUAGGGAUGCUGUGUCAAUGUGGAUCAGGCAAUGGUACUUUGAAAGGUCAUCAUUAUAAUUUUAUUAAGCUGUGAUGAGAGU